AAAUGAUGCUCCAGUGGCAGGAGCAACUCAAGUUCAUCAUUGUCCUGAGAGAGAGGAGCAGCGCGGUUCUCGGCCGGGACAGCAGAACGCCAGGGGACCCUCACCUGGGCGCGCCGGGGCACGGGCUUUGAUUGUCCUGGGGUCGCGGAGACCCGCGCGCCUGCCCUGCACGCCGGGCGGCAACCUUUGCAGUCGCGUUGGCUGCUGCGAUCGGCCGGCGGGUCCCUGCCGAAGGCUCGGCUGCUUCUGUCCACCUCUUACACUUCUUCAUUUAUCGGUGGAUCAUUUCGAGAGUCCGUCUUGUAAAUGUUUGGCACUUUGCUACUUUAUUGCUUCUUUCUGGCGACAGUUCCAGCACUCGCCGAGACCGGCGGAGAAAGGCAGCUGAGCCCGGAGAAGAGCGAAAUAUGGGGACCCGGGCUAAAAGCAGACGUCGUCCUUCCCGCCCGCUAUUUCUAUAUUCAGGCAGUGGAUACAUCAGGGAAUAAAUUCACAUCUUCUCCAGGCGAAAAGGUCUUCCAGGUGAAAGUCUCAGCACCAGAGGAGCAAUUCACUAGAGUUGGAGUCCAGGUUUUAGACCGAAAAGAUGGGUCCUUCAUAGUAAGAUACAGAAUGUAUGCAAGCUACAAAAAUCUGAAGGUGGAAAUUAAAUUCCAAGGGCAACAUGUGGCCAAAUCCCCAUAUAUUUUAAAAGGGCCGGUUUACCAUGAGAACUGUGACUGUCCUCUGCAAGAUAGUGCAGCCUGGCUACGGGAGAUGAACUGCCCUGAAACCAUUGCUCAGAUUCAGAGAGAUCUGGCACAUUUCCCUGCUGUGGAUCCAGAAAAGAUUGCAGUAGAAAUCCCAAAAAGAUUUGGACAGAGGCAGAGCCUAUGUCACUACACCUUAAAGGAUAACAAGGUUUAUAUCAAGACUCAUGGUGAACAUGUAGGUUUUAGAAUUUUCAUGGAUGCCAUACUACUUUCUUUGACUAGAAAGGUAGUUAUAUAGCAUCAAUAUUAAGCCUCCUUUAAACUAAGACAUCAGAGUACCGUCAUACUUCUCUUGCUCCUCUUUGUCAAUCCAUGGGAAAAUGAGAAUGUUCUUCAGGACUUCGGUUUCUCAAGAUGCUUCUCAGACUGGUGAAGAUGCCAGAUGUGGAGCUCUUUGUUAAUUUGGGAGACUGGCCUUUGGAAAAAAAGAAAUCCAAUUCAAACAUCCAUCCGAUCUUUUCCUGGUGUGGCUCCACAGAUUCCAAGGAUAUCGUGAUGCCUACGUACGAUUUGACUGAUUCUGUUCUGGAAACCAUGGGCCGGGUAAGUCUGGAUAUGAUGUCCGUGCAAGCUAACACGGGUCCUCCCUGGGAAAGCAAAAAUUCCACUGCCGUCUGGAGAGGGCGAGACAGCCGCAAAGAGAGACUCGAGCUGGUUAAACUCAGUAGAAAACACCCAGAACUCAUAGACGCUGCUUUCACCAACUUUUUCUUCUUUAAACACGAUGAAAACCUGUAUGGUCCCAUUGUGAAACAUAUUUCAUUUUUUGAUUUCUUCAAGCAUAAGUAUCAAAUAAAUAUCGAUGGCACUGUAGCAGCUUAUCGCCUGCCAUAUUUGCUAGUUGGUGACAGUGUUGUGCUGAAGCAGGAUUCCAUCUACUAUGAACAUUUUUACAAUGAGCUGCAGCCCUGGAAACACUACAUUCCAGUUAAGAGCAACCUGAGCGAUCUGCUAGAAAAACUUAAAUGGGCGAAAGAUCACGAUGAAGAGGCCAAAAAGAUAGCAAAAGCAGGACAAGAAUUUGCAAGAAAUAAUCUCAUGGGCGAUGACAUAUUCUGUUAUUAUUUCAAACUUUUCCAGGAAUAUGCCAAUUUACAAGUGAGUGAGCCCCAAAUCCGAGAGGGCAUGAAAAGGGUAGAACCACAGACUGAGGACGACCUCUUCCCUUGUACUUGCCAUAGGAAAAAGACCAAAGAUGAACUCUGAUAUGCAAAAUAACUUCUAUUAGAAUAAUGGUGCUCUGAAGACUCUUCUUAACUAAAAAGAAGAAUUUUUUUAAGUAUUAAUUCCAUGGACAAUAUAAAAUCUGUGUGAUUGUUUGCAGUAUGAAGACACAUUUCUACUUAUGCAGUAUUCUCAUGACUGUACUUUAAAGUACAUUUUUAGAAUUUUAUAAUAAAACCACCUUUAUUUUAAAGGA